GCCGCCGCGCACGCCAUGGGAGCCGUGACUGACGGUGAGGCCCCGCUCGCCGCCACACGCGCCCGCUGCACGGCCCGCUGGGCCUCCCCUGAGACCCCUGGCCUCCCGGCCCGCUUCCGGGAACCCCUCGGCCUCCCCGGCCUCUUCGCCAGAGCGCUUCGGCCUUCCCGACCUCUCCCCGGAGCCCCGGGCCUCCCCGGCUGCUUCCCUGAGUCCUUCCUCCUCUCGCCAGAGCCCGAGCGCCCCUCGGAGACCCUCGGCUUUCCCCGUCCGCUCUCCCGGAGGCAGCGCGGGGCUAUAGGACGAAGUUAUACGGAAGCGUCUCCUCAUUGAUGGAGAUGGUGCUGGAGAUGAUCGGAGAAUUAAUCUGCUAGUGAAGAGUUUCAUUAAAUGGUGCAACUCUGGGUCCCAGGAAGAGGGAUAUAGCCAGUACCAACGUAUGCUGAGCACGCUGUCUCAAUGUGAAUUUUCAAUGGGCAAAACUUUACUAGUAUAUGAUAUGAAUCUCAGAGAAAUGGAAAAUUAUGAAAAAAUUUACAAGGAAAUAGAAUGUAGCAUAGCUGGAGCACAUGAAAAAAUUGCUGAGUGCAAAAAGCAAAUUCUUCAAGCAAAACGAAUACGAAAAAAUCGCCAAGAAUAUGAUGCUUUGGCAAAAGUGAUUCAGCACCAUCCAGACAGGCAUGAGACAUUAAAGGAACUAGAGGCUCUGGGAAAAGAAUUAGAGCAUCUUUCACACAUUAAAGAAAGUGUUGAAGAUAAGCUGGAAUUGAGACGGAAACAGUUUCAUGUUCUUCUUAGUACCAUCCAUGAACUUCAGCAAACAUUGGAAAAUGAUGAAAAACUCUCAGAGGUAGAAGAAGCUCAGGAAGCAAGCAUGGAAACAGAUCCUAAGCCAUAGACAGGCUAAUUGCCCACCACUCCCAGGAAUAUUGAAAUAGCUACAUGACCAUAAUGUGUUUAAAAUGUGGUAUGCUCUUGAGAUAUUUAAAGUUUUGGCAGUAAAAUACUCUGUUUUUAAGUAUGAAUGUAUUUCAUUCAUAUUUCCUCUCACAAAGGAAAAUGACUUCAGUAUAGAUUUGUUUUUAUUAAAAUGCAUUUUUUAUUCUUAAGUGGUAGGAAGCAACAUCCAAAAAUGCUUAAUAAAAUGCUUUUAAGCUGCA